AUUAACACUUGGGUAACUUACCCUUCACAAUCCAUCUAAAUCCUUCUCAAUUGCUGCCACCAUGACUCGUUACUUCUGCUGUGGAAGCUACUUCCCAGGAUACCCUAUCUAUGGGACCAACUUCCAUGGGACCUUCAGAGCCACCCCCUUGAACUGUGUUGUGCCUCUGGGCUCUCCCCUGAACUAUGGCUGUGGAUGCAAUGGCUACAGCUCCCUGGGCUACAGCUUUGGUGGUAGCAACAUCAACAACCUGGGCGGCUGCUAUGGUGGUAGCUUCUAUAGGCCAUGGGGCUCUGGCUCUGGCUUUGGCUACAGCACCUACUGAUGGACCAAUGGCUCCAGUGACUACAGGACUCUCAAUUAAUUCUCUGCACAGAACAACCUGAAGAGCAAUGACUGUCUUCCUACCUUCCCAUGUGCUUGGGUGAUACAUCUUCCAUCUUCUUGCUGACUUCUUGCUGUGGUCUUUGUCUUUGAUGCUGUUGGACAAGUCACCCAGGACUCAGGUGCUGAACUGAUACUCAUCUACAGACAAAGGAAGCAAGAUGCAUUUUUUUGGUCAUACUUGAAUUUUAACAGUGAAAAAGUAGUUUGCCUCCCAUGGUUGCUCUGCUCAUGUAUUAUUAGCUUCUACAUCAACAUUAAUGUAUUACAAAUUGGGUGUGGGUAGUAAGGGGAUUUUCUGUCAGUCUCUUAAUAAAUCUAUUUCCUUCAGCAUAAA